CCACGUCCCCGUGCUGUGUGCUCCAGCCCACCGUCCCGGCCUCCGGGCACCCGGAGCUCCCAGUACCAGAGCACGUGUGCCGGGGACAUCUCCAGGCAAGGGCACAGGCCACAGCCACCCAGGGCAGCCCCUGCUGUUGGCACCCCUCACUGCGGUCCUGUCACUCUGUCUGUAGCGAGGGGGGAGGCAGGGGCCAAGGCGGCGGCUGUCUUGCAGGGUGUUGGGUUGCAGGUGUGGCCGUGUCUGUCCUGAGCCCUCUGCUCCAAGGGUCUUGCUGACCACAGUUAUGCUUCUGGGGCCUGGUGUCCCUGCACUGGCAGUGGGCGGGGAAGAGGCUUCUCUGAGGGUUCAGCAGCAGCUCCCAGUGUGACACUGGGGAGUGCCUGCUCUGCCAACACCAGGCUGGAGGCAGGUUUUAGGGAAGGCUGGGCUUUCCCGGCCUCAGAGCUGCACCCAUGCUACCUGUGAGCUUCUGGGGCCUCCUGGAGCCUCGAGAUGGCGUGGAACGGCCAGGGUCGUCGGUGGUGAGCCAGCAGCCCUGUCACCCACACCUCAUCACUGUUCCCUCAGGCAAACGUGGUGUGUGUGGUGUAUGACGUCUCUGAGGAGGCCACCAUUGAGAAGAUUCGAACUAAGUGGAUCCCACUGGUGAAUGGGGGGACCACGCAGGGGCCCAGUGGGCAACAAGUCAGACCUGCGGUCGGGGAGCUCCAUGGAGGCCGUGCUCCCCAUCAUGAGCCAGUUUCCCGAGAUUGAGACCUGCGUGGAGUGUUCGGCCAAGAACCUGAGGAACAUCUCAGAGCUGUUCUACUACGCCCAGAAGGCCGUCCUGCAUCCCACAGCCCCCCUCUAUGACCCUGAGGCCAAGCAGUUGAGGCCCGCGUGCGCCCAGGCGCUGACGCGCAUCUUCAGGCUCUCAGAUCAGGACCUGGACCAGGCGCUCAGUGACGAAGAGCUCAACGCUUUCCAGCAGAAAUCCUGCUUUGGGCACCCCCUGGCCCCGCAGGCCCUGGAGGACGUGAAGACGGUGGUGUGCAGGAACGUGGCGGGCGGCGUGCGGGAGGACCGGCUGACCCUGGAUGGUUUCCUCUUCCUGAACACGCUCUUCAUCCAGCGCGGCCGGCACGAGACCACCUGGACCAUCCUGCGGCGCUUCGGCUACAGCGAUGCCCUGGAGCUGACUGCGGACUAUCUCUCCCCUCUGAUCCACGUGCCCCCCGGCUGCAGCACGGAGCUCAACCACCUUGGCUACCAGUUUGUGCAGAGAGUGUUUGAGAAGCACGACCAGGACCGCGACGGCGCCCUCUCGCCCGUGGAGCUGCAAAGCCUUUUCAGUGUGUUCCCAGCAGCGCCCUGGGGCCCCGAGCUCCCACGCACAGUCCGCACAGAGGCCGGCCGGUUGCCCCUGCACGGAUACCUCUGCCAGUGGACCCUGGUGACCUACCUGGACGUCCGGAGCUGCCUUGGACACCUAGGCUACCUGGGCUACCCCACCCUCUGUGAGCAGGACCAGGCCCAUGCCAUCACAGUCACUCGUGAGAAGAGGCUGGACCAGGAGAAGGGACAGACGCAGCGGAGCGUCCUCCUGUGCAAGGUGGUAGGGGCCCGUGGAGUGGGCAAGUCUGCCUUCCUGCAGGCCUUUCUCGGCCGCGGCCUGGGGCACCAGGACACGAGGGAGCAGCCUCCCGGCUACGCCAUCGACACGGUGCAGGUCAAUGGACAGGAGAAGUACUUGAUCCUCUGUGAGGUGGGCACAGAUGGUCUGCUGGCCACAUCGCUGGACGCCACCUGUGACGUUGCCUGCUUGAUGUUUGAUGGCAGUGACCCAAAGUCCUUUGCACAUUGUGCCAGCGUCUACAAGCACCAUUACAUGGACGGGCAGACCCCCUGCCUCUUUGUCUCCUCCAAGGCCGACCUGCCCGAAGGUGUCGCGGUGUCUGGCCCAUCACCGGCCGAGUUUUGCCGCAAGCACCGGCUACCCGCUCCCGUGCCGUUCUCCUGUGCUGGCCCAGCCGAGCCCAGCACCACCAUCUUCACCCAGCUCGCCACCAUGGCCGCCUUCCCACAUUUGGUCCACGCAGAGCUGCAUCCCUCUUCCUUCUGGCUCCGGGGGCUGCUGGGGGUUGUCGGGGCCGCCGUGGCCGCAGUCCUCAGCUUCUCACUCUACAGGGUCCUGGUGAAGAGCCAGUGAGGCCCCUGGUACCCAAGCCCCCUCCCCUGACCUGGGUGUGCCUCGCUGCUGGGGCUCUGCAGGGGCAGCACAGCUGGGGUGCAGGCCAGGCUGCCACUCCGGGAACGCCUUUGCGCCGGGACUUUUUGUUUCUGAAGGCAGUCGAUCUGCAGCGGGGCCUUAUGCUGCCAUGCACUGCCCUGGCUCCUGCCGGACCCCCAGGGUGGGCCGUGGCAGGUGGCUGAGCAGGAGCUCCCAAGUGCCGGCCACCGCUGUCAGGGAUUGCCCACCCCUGGGCAUCAUGUGUGUGGGGCCGGGGAGCACAGGUGUGGGAGCUGGUGACCCCAGACCCAGAAUUCUCAGGGCUCUACCCCCCUUUCCUGGUCCUAGGUGGCCAGUGGGUAUGAGGAGGGCUGGAAGGCAGAGCUUUGGGCCAAAAGCAGGCGUUGGGGGGUCCCCCCUCAAGUUUGGAGCCGUUUCCGUGGUUGUAGCAGAGGACCGGAGGUUGGGUUCCUGAUUAAACUUCACUGUGUGUUUUCUAUCUCGGAUCCCAGUCUCUGAAGACAACUUGCUUUGAUUCAACCUAGAA